GCGGCAUACUCAGCGGCAGAGACGGAAGAACAGCGCUCCCGAGGCCGCGGGAGCCUGCAGAGAGGACAGCCGGCCUGCGCCGGGACAUGCGGCCCCAGGAGCUCCCCAGGCUCGCGUUCCCGUUGCUGCUGUUGCUGUUGCUGCUGCUGCCGCCGCCGCCGUGCCCUGCCCACAGCGCCACGCGCUUCGACCCCACCUGGGAGUCCCUGGACGCCCGCCAGCUGCCCGCGUGGUUUGACCAGGCCAAGUUCGGCAUCUUCAUCCACUGGGGAGUGUUUUCCGUGCCCAGCUUCGGUAGCGAGUGGUUCUGGUGGUAUUGGCAAAAGGAAAAGAUACCGAAGUAUGUGGAAUUUAUGAAAGAUAAUUACCCUCCUAGUUUCAAAUAUGAAGAUUUUGGACCACUAUUUACAGCAAAAUUUUUUAAUGCCAACCAGUGGGCAGAUAUUUUUCAGGCCUCUGGUGCCAAAUACAUUGUCUUAACUUCCAAACAUCAUGAAGGCUUUACCUUGUGGGGGUCAGAAUAUUCGUGGAACUGGAAUGCCAUAGAUGAGGGGCCCAAGAGGGACAUUGUCAAGGAACUUGAGGUAGCCAUUAGGAACAGAACUGACCUGCGUUUUGGACUGUACUAUUCCCUUUUUGAAUGGUUUCAUCCGCUCUUCCUUGAGGAUGAAUCCAGUUCAUUCCAUAAGCGGCAAUUUCCAGUUUCUAAGACAUUGCCAGAGCUCUAUGAGUUAGUGAACAACUAUCAGCCUGAGGUUCUGUGGUCGGAUGGUGACGGAGGAGCACCGGAUCAAUACUGGAACAGCACAGGCUUCUUGGCCUGGUUAUAUAAUGAAAGCCCAGUUCGGGGCACAGUAGUCACCAAUGAUCGUUGGGGAGCUGGUAGCAUCUGUAAGCAUGGUGGCUUCUAUACCUGCAGUGAUCGUUAUAACCCAGGACAUCUUUUGCCACAUAAAUGGGAAAACUGCAUGACAAUAGACAAACUGUCCUGGGGCUAUAGGAGGGAAGCUGGAAUCUCUGACUAUCUUACAAUUGAAGAAUUGGUGAAGCAACUUGUAGAGACAGUUUCAUGUGGAGGAAAUCUUUUGAUGAAUAUUGGGCCCACACUAGAUGGCACCAUUUCUGUAGUUUUUGAGGAGCGACUGAGGCAAAUGGGGUCCUGGCUAAAAGUCAAUGGAGAAGCUAUUUAUGAAACCCAUACCUGGCGAUCCCAGAAUGACACUGUCACCCCAGAUGUGUGGUACACAUCCAAGCCUAAAGAAAAAUUAGUCUAUGCCAUUUUUCUUAAAUGGCCCACAUCAGGACAGCUGUUCCUUGGCCAUCCCAAAGCUAUUCUGGGGGCAACAGAGGUGAAACUACUGGGCCAUGGACAGCCACUUAACUGGAUUUCUUUGGAGCAAAAUGGCAUUAUGGUAGAACUGCCACAGCUAACCAUUCAUCAGAUGCCGUGUAAAUGGGGCUGGGCUCUAGCCCUGACUAAUGUGAUCUAAAGUGCAGCAGAGUGGCUGAUGCUGCAAGUUAUGUCUAAGGCUAGGAACUAUCAGGUGUCUAUAAUUGUAGCACAUGGAGAAAGCAAAUGUAAAACUGGAUAAGAAAAUUAUUUUGGCAGUUCAGCCCUUUCCCUUUUUCCCACUAAAUUUUUUCUUAAAUUACCCAUGUAACCAUUUUAACUCUCCAGUGCACUUUGCCAUUAAAGUCUCUUCACAUUGAUUUGUUUCCAUGUGUGACUCAGAGGUGAGAAUUUUUUCACAUUAUAGUAGCAAGGAAUUGGUGGUAUUAUGGACCGAACUGAAAAUUUUAUGUUGAAGCCAUAUCCCCCAUGAUUAUAUAGUUAUGCAUCACUUAAUAUGGGGAUAUUUUCUGGGAAAUGCAUUGCUAGUCAAUUUUUUUUUGUGCCAACAUCAUAGAGUGUAUUUACAAAAUCCUAGAUGGCAUAGCCUACUACACACCUAAUGUGUAUGGUAUAGACUGUUGCUCCUAGGCUACAGACAUAUACAGCAUGUUACUGAAUACUGUAGGCAAUAGUAACAGUGGUAUUUGUAUAUCGAAACAUAUGGAAACAUAGAGAAGGUACAGUAAAAAUACUGUAAAAUAAAUGGUGCACCUGUAUAGGGCACUUACCACGAAUGGAGCUUACAGGACUGGAAGUUGCUCUGGGUGAGUCAGUGAGUGAAUGUGAAGGCCUAGGACAUUAUUGAACACUGCCAGACUUUAUAAAUACUGUAUGCUUAGGCUACACUACAUUUAUAAAAAAAAGUUUUUCUUUCUUCAAUUAUAAAUUAACAUAAGUGUACUGUAACUUUACAAACGUUUUAAUUUUUAAAACCUUUUUGGCUCUUUUGUAAUAACACUUAGCUUAAAACAUAAACUCAUUGUGCAAAUGUA